GGGUUUUCCACGUUGGACAAGUGCGGCUCGGCGGCCAGCGGAGCGCGCCCCUUCCCGCUGCCCGCUCCGCUCCUCUCUUCUACCCAGCCCAGUGGGCGAGUGGGCAGCGGCGGCCGCGGCGCUGGGCCCUCUCCCGCCGGUGUGUGCGCGCUCGUACGCGCGGCCCCCGGCGCCAGCCCCGCCGCCUGAGAGGGGGCCUGCGCCGCCGGCCGGGGCGUGCGCCCGGGAGCCACCGCCACCGCGGCCCGCGCCCUCAGGCGCUGGGGUCCCCGCGGACCCGGAGGCGGCGGACGGGCUCGGCAGAUGUAGCCGCCGGGCCGAAGCAGGAGCCGGCGGGGGGGCGCCGGGAGAGCGAGGGCUUUGCAUUUUGCAGUGCUAUUUUUUGAGGGGGGCGGGGGGUGGAGGAAGCGGAAAGCCGCGCCGAGUCGCCGGGGACCUCCGGGGUGAACCAUGUUGAGUCCUGCCAACGGGGAGCAGCUCCACCUGGUGAACUAUGUGGAGGACUACCUGGACUCCAUCGAGUCCCUGCCUUUCGACUUGCAGAGAAAUGUCUCGCUGAUGCGGGAGAUCGACGCGAAAUACCAAGAGAUCCUGAAGGAGCUAGACGAGUGCUACGAGCGCUUCAGUCGCGAGACAGACGGGGCGCAGAAGCGGCGGAUGCUGCACUGUGUGCAGCGCGCGCUGAUCCGCAGCCAGGAGCUGGGCGACGAGAAGAUCCAGAUCGUGAGCCAGAUGGUGGAGCUGGUGGAGAACCGCACGCGGCAGGUGGACAGCCACGUGGAGCUGUUCGAGGCGCAGCAGGAGCUGGGCGACACAGCGGGCAACAGCGGCAAGGCUGGCGCGGACAGGCCCAAAGGCGAGGCGGCAGCGCAGGCUGACAAGCCCAACAGCAAGCGCUCACGGCGGCAGCGCAACAACGAGAACCGUGAGAACGCGUCCAGCAACCACGACCACGACGACGGCGCCUCGGGCACACCCAAGGAGAAGAAGGCCAAGACCUCCAAGAAGAAGAAGCGCUCCAAGGCCAAGGCGGAGCGAGAGGCGUCCCCUGCCGACCUCCCCAUCGACCCCAACGAACCCACGUACUGUCUGUGCAACCAGGUCUCCUAUGGGGAGAUGAUCGGCUGCGACAACGACGAGUGCCCCAUCGAGUGGUUCCACUUCUCGUGCGUGGGGCUCAAUCAUAAACCCAAGGGCAAGUGGUACUGUCCCAAGUGCCGGGGGGAGAACGAGAAGACCAUGGACAAAGCCCUGGAGAAAUCCAAAAAAGAGAGGGCUUACAACAGGUAGUUUGUGGACAGGCGCCUGGUGUGAGGAGGACAAAAUAAACCGUGUAUUUAUUACAUUGCUGCCUUUGUUGAGGUGCAAGGAGUGUAAAAUGUAUAUUUUUAAAGAAUGUUAGUAAAGGAACCAUUCCUUUCAUAGGGAUGGCAGUGAUUCUGUUUGCCUUUUGUUUUCAUUGGUACACGUGUAACAAGAAAGUGGUCUGUGGAUCAGCAUUUUAGAAACUACAAAUAUAGGUUUGAUUCAACACUUAAGUCUCAGACUGAUUUCUUGCGGGAGGAGGGGGACUAAACUCAACCUAACACAUUAAAUGUGGAAGGAAAAUAUUUCAUUUAGCUUUUUUAUUUUAAUACAAGUAAUAUUAUUACUUUAUGAACAAUUUUUUUUAAUUGGCCAUGUCGCCAAAAAUACAGCCUAUAGUAAAUGUGUUUCUUGCUGCCAUGAUGUAUAUCCAUAUAACAAUUCAGUAACAAAGGUUUAAAGUUUGAAGAUUAUUUUUUAAAAAGGUAAAUGGUUAAAUUUUACAUGACAGAUAUUUUAUCUAUUGGCCUGUUCCCCAAAUGGCCAUUUUAAAAUGCUUGGGUACACUUCUCUUAAGUGGUCUAGUCAAGGAACCUCAAGUCAUGCUUUUGCUAUCACCAAUCAUAGUGUACCCAUCUUUAAUUUAUAUCAGGUGUAUAAAUGUACAUUUCCAAAUGAACUUGCACUUGUUAUAUUAUAAUUGGAAGUGCAGUCAGCAGAUGCUGUUGUGAAGCUAAUGUCACAAUUAUGUGCAAAGGUGUGCUUCCUGCUGUAUGUGAGCUGUAAAAAUGUUACGUGAAGAAAUAAAUGAAACUUGGCCAGUUUGUUCCUCUAGUAGUAUAUUUAAUUUUGACAUAAGUAACUUUUAAAAUUUGUCUUAAAAAUUUAUACACCAGCAAUUUAGACAAAGCCUUAAGCAAAUUUUGUAUUAUUGUUCUCACUUAUUAUUAAUAAUGAAGUAGAAGUUACUUAAUUGCCAGCAAAUAAAUACGUGUCAAAAAAGAAUCUGUAUUCAGACCCUGGGUCAGGAAAUUACUGCCCACUUGUCAAGUUCAGCCCACCAUCUGUUUGAAGAUUAUAUGAAGUUUAAAUUCUAGUGUCCAUAAAUAAAGUUUCAGCGGAACACAGCCGUGCUUAUGUGCGUAUGUAUUGUCUGACUGCUUUUGCAAAACGGCAGAGUUCAAUAGUUGCACCUGAAACCAUUUGACUUGACAAGCCAAAACUAUUUUCUGGCCCUCUGCAGAAAGGGUUUGCUGACCUCUGAUUUAGACUAGCAUCUAACAUUGAUUUGCCCACAUAUUGAAAGGGUCAGUGGAGUUUUCAUUUAUUAUUUUUUAUUUUUUUGAGAUUGAGUUCCAGGCUGGAGUGCAAUAGCGCAAUCUUGGCUCACCGCAACCUCCGCCUCCCAGGUUCAAGCGAUUGUCCUGCCUCAGCCUCCCCAGUAGCUAGGAUUACAGGCAUGCACCACCACGCCUGGCUAAUUUUGUAUUUUCAGUAGAGACGCGGUUUCUCCAUGUUGGUCAUGGCUGGUCUCGCACUCCCGACCUCAGGUGAUCCACCUGCCUCAGCCUUCCAAAGUGCUGGGAUUACAGGUGUGAGCCACCGUGCCCGGCUGGAGUUUUCAUUUUUUUUUUUUUUUUUUUUUCUGAGAUGGAGUCUCACUCUGUCUCCAGGCUAGAGUGCAGUGGCCCAGUCUUGGCUCACUGCAACCUCUGCCUCUCGGGUUCAAGCGAUUCUCUUGCCUCAGCCUCCCGAGUAGCUGGGACUACAGGUGCGUGCCACCAUGCCCAGCUAAUUUUUGUAUUUUUAGUAGAGAUGGGUUUUCACCAUGUUGGCCAGUAUGGUCUCGAGCUCUUGACCAUGAUCCGCCCACCUCGGCCUCCCACAGUGCUGGGAUUACAGGCGUGAGCCACCGUGCGCUGAGUGAUACGUGGUUCCCUUUAACUUCGCACAUGGUAAAAUCAGUUUCUUUCCAUGAUCUGUUUCACAGUCUCUGUGAAGCUACCUACCACAAAGAAGUAGUGAGUGAUGACUUUCUAGAAUCUAAGUAUAUGGCAUGUAUUUAUUAUAAGUAAAACAUUAAGUUUGCUGAUUGUUUACUUGUGAUAAACAAUUAUUGUGAACUUUAUUUGUGCUGGACAUAAGUGUCUGUUUUACAGUGAAAUUCCAUUAUAGAGGGUUACUUGGUAGAGAAAUGCAAAUUGUAGUUGGUCAUAUACUAAAAUUUGAACUUUUUACAUAUCAAUACUUACAAAUAGGUGUUUAUUUUCCCACAAAACUCCAGAACAUUUAAGAGUCUCGGGUGUUUAAAUUUGAUGAGAUUUACCCAAACAAAUAGUGAACAAAAGGUUUAUGAAAAUAAGUUAUGAAACUAAAAUACUUAAUAAACAUCCAGUGACAAUAAAAAUAGCUUGAGUCUUUGCUUAUAUAAAAUUUCAUGCUAAUUUUUCACUUCUAUAUUAAUUGGAGGUAAUAAUGCAAAUUAAGUUAUAGAAAUGAAGAUUCAAUGAAAUGCAGUUGCUCAUCCUGGAUUUCUUCAUAUUCAGUUUUGGUGUAGACAACUGGUGAAGAGAGAUGGCUCAGAGGCCAAGCCUUGCAAUCUAGGAGCCCAGCCCUGUCCUUUAAGGGCUUGAUCUUGAAUAAAUUGCUUAACAGUUGGUCUAUAGUUCUACACUUUUAAAGUAUGUUUCACAGAGGGUGGUUCCAAUAAAUAAAUGCACUGGCAUAUUCAAAUGUUGGAUAAUUUUUCUCUAGCUUUCUUCAAGUUUCUCAUAAGGACAGGUGGGUAGCCACUUAUUCUUUAAAAAAAAAUAGAUACAAUACAGAGUCGUGUUGGACUGGCAGUCUUAAAUCACUCUUGUUAUUUCCAGUGGACAUUAAAAAAAAAUCACAGAUAAGUACUUAAAACACUCAAGAUUUGGGAUUUAGAUCAUGAUUAGAUACAAUAGAAAGAUCCUGGAAUCCCGACAUGAGGACAAAAAUGGUACUGAAUUCUUUUUGAAAAAUAGAUUACUGAAAAGCGAUCUAAUAUAGAACAGUUGCUUUUACUUAGAUGUUCAAUGCAUAUUUGUUGUAUAAUAACCAAGUUAUUACAGUUCAGAUAAAGGGUCCAAAGUGUUUUCGUUAUGAUAUAAUACUUUCUAUUGUAAACUGGACUAAAGAAACGUUGUAUGUUCAAGGAAGUGUUGAGCAGCCAUGGUGUUCCUGGGACAGGCUCCCCAGGUGCUGAGAGAGGUGCUGCAGGAGUCACAGACCUGCAGGCACGCACUUGCCAGUGACUGGGACGUUGGCUGGUGGUUCUCUUUUGGUGUGAUUAGAGCUAUGUGAGUUGUCUCAAUACUUGAGACUGUCGGUGGUUGCCAAUGCUGAAUAAAGCAUUUAUCAAAGUAAAA